GACCACUGGUAGCGGCAGCAGCUCGCGCCCGCGCCCUCCUCGUACCCGUGCGCCCCCGGAGACCGAUCCCGCCCCGCGGCCCAGGCCGGGCCUGGUGAGAGCCGCGGGGGGAGGGGCCGCGUCCGGCUCCGGAACCGGGAGAGGCGCCGAGGGGUGUGGGGUGAGGGCCGCCCGUGGGGUCCCGGCGAGUCUGCGAGCCGCUCUCGCCCGGGGCGCACAGGCUCGAGUCCUCGUUUCAGGGCCGGCCCCCGGCUGGGCGGAGCCGAGACCCGCUGGCGGGGCUCGCGGCGUCGGGGUCUGGGGUCCGGUCCUCGCGGGGCCAGAACCCAGCGGGUGCCGCUUCUCCACCCGAGGCUUCCACCUCCAACGAGCCAUGUUCCAGGCUGCAGGAGCCGCCCAGGCCACCCCCUCUCAUGACGCCAAAGGCGGCGGCAGCAGCACGGUGCAGCGCUCCAAGUCCUUCAGCCUGCGGGCCCAGGUGAAGGAGACCUGCGCCGCCUGCCAGAAGACCGUGUACCCCAUGGAGCGGCUGGUGGCCGACAAGCUCAUUUUCCACAACUCUUGCUUCUGCUGCAAGCACUGUCACACCAAGCUCAGCCUGGGCAGCUACGCCGCGCUGCACGGGGAGUUCUACUGCAAACCCCACUUCCAGCAGCUGUUUAAGAGCAAAGGCAACUACGACGAGGGGUUUGGCCGCAAGCAGCACAAGGAGCUCUGGGCCCACAAGGAGGUGGACCCCGGCACCAAGACGGCCUGAGGCCUCUGUAACCUUCCACCCCCUCUGCGGAAGGCCUGGAGCCGGCAGGGGGAAGGUGGGAAGGAGGUCGAGCUGGGCUUGCGUGGGGGCCAGGUGGGAAGGGGAUGAGGCUUGCUCAGGCGUAGGGGACCAGGGCAGGGCUCUGCUCCAGGACUCCUUCCUUCUUCCUUCUCCCGCAGCCGGUGAGGGUUUGGAAACCAGGAUUGGGGUCUGCCCACCACCCUGCUUCCUGCUUCGUUCAGCCUCCCUCCCCACCUCACCCCAGGACCCCCUGGGAGGCCCCCAAGCCCAGCUCCCCUAUCUAGGUGCCUUUUCUCCAGCAAGGAGUCAGCAUGCCCCCCUCAGGGUCCCAAGCUCCCUCACUGCCACCGGAGACUGUGUGGCCCCCACGUCUCCCCAUCUACCUCUACCCUUAACCUGUUUCUGAGCCACGGAGACAGGGAGGAAGGAGCGCGACAGUGCCACCUGUUGGGCAUCAUAAAUGCCCCUGCAGCCCAUGGGGGAGGAGAUGGGGAAGUGGAGCCACCCUGCCUCUGCAGGGCAAGGCAGGGCCUGCCCCAGUGGGGCUUGGGACCAUCUCGAACCACCAGCGUGGAGAAGCAGAAGCAAAAGCACUCGCCAGGCUGCAGCCUCAGGCACUGGCAGGGGCUGGUGCGGCCCCACUCCCCUCCCCCGCUCCCAUUUGUGCCCAUCCUGUUGUGACCAACCCCGUUUUAAACAUGUUUCAAUAGAUCCAGAUUCUCUAUUGUGUGGCCUGCUGGGGGAUCUGUCACAGGAAGGGUGCAGACUCACCAUGGGGCGGGCAUGGGGGGACAGGGCCAGCCCCGACUACCUCGGCCCUGAUGGGGGCAGGGAGCUAGAAGUGGGUGUCAGUUCCCUGACACACCAUUGAGAAAUGGGAGGGCUCCUCUUCACAGCGAGGGCUUCAUGCUGUCACACCCACAGUGGUUUUGGAACUGAAACUCCACCUCACCCCUCAGUUCUGGGUUGGUUCAGACCCACCAACUUACCAUAUGCACCCCAUUGUGAAGAGGCCUGAGAGCGGGAGGGCCAGGCUGCCAGUGGGUGAUGGCGCCUGUCCUCGCUGCACUUCAGUGCCUGGGGUGCAAGCUGCCGCGUUCCCUGGCUGGUUCCAGCUGUCUAGCUCCCUCCCUUCUUCCCAGCCCUUUGACCUGGAAGUAAGUUAGCGAAGAAUGGCGGUAACCAGCAGACCCAGCAAGUGCUGCCCAAGGUUUUAGUGACCCCUGGAUUGUCCCCCCUCAUCAUUACCCCUCGCUGCUGUCAUCAUCCCCUUGCCUUUUCAAGCUCUGCGGAGGUGCAGUCACAGCUACUGUCUCAGGAAAUCCAAAGAGAAACUACCUCUGCUUCUCUGAAAACCCAGGGACAAUGAGGGAUGAGUUCACAGCAGAGCAAACCAGGCAAGUUGGGAGGACCUGAGGGCGCCCCGGUGGGACACAGGCAGAAGUCUGGGUUGUCCUGCUCCAGAUUCAACUUCCUGAUGUCUCCAGACAUGGGAUCGAUGAGAACAGAGACUCCUGGAGGGUUUGCUGCCACCACACCAUACAACUGCCUGAGUUCCUAAGUGGCCUCCCCGUGGAACAGGGCAGGGAGCUGGGCCACAGGCUCCAGUGUCACAUAAGUCACUAUGCUGAGGCAGGCACUGCUCCUCGAGGGAGCAGAGCGAAUACUCAGCAGAGAUGGUGCCCCGGCCUGGAUCCUCCCAAGUGUGAAGUGAGCGCCUCAGAGCCUCUCAGGGCAGGCCAACUUCCUGCACCAGAGGUCUCAGAUGGCAAGGAUCAUCUUGGUUCGGUUAAGCAACAGUAGCAGAUGACCACAAGGGGGUACUGGAGAGGUGGCUCUUGGAGACACCUGACCCCUGCCCUGCAAAGAUGGGACUGAAGGAAGUCCUCUGGGCCAGGAAGACCCUACCAAAUAUCAUGAAAGCUCCGGGAACUCAGCCACUGGUGACGUUCAGGUUGUGAGGGCCAGCAGUGCCACCCUGGUAAAUCAGCCCUGUUGGGACCACCCCAGUGGAGCUCCUGGAGGGGCAACUGGAGGAAAGGGGCAGACACCUCUGGACUGACAAUGGUAUCAGCCAGAUCACCCCAGGACCCCUCUACUUGGAGUCAAGUUCUCUUCUGCUUGAAAGGCCCAGGCUCGUUGCCAGGCACCAUACCUGGCCCCUGCUAAGCAAAAACCUACCUCCACCCCCCACAACUGAAAGCACUGCCACAGGACCCCUCUGAUAUAAAUGAUCCCUUUUAUUGUAAGUAAUGCGCAACACUGGCCUGGCUUUGCACUGCAAGCCCUCGGUCAAGAUAUAGUCAAAUAACUAUGGCUGCAGGUUCCACAGUUCCACAAUAACCAUGGCUGCACGAUCCACAAUUCAGACACAGACAUAGAGCUGGGGUGGGUGGAAGGGGCAGGAGGGUGGCAGAGUGCGGACUGUCCCCAGCCCUGGCCUCUCCAUGCAGAGUUGGCCCAGGCAGACACACCCCAUGGAAUGAUGAGAAAGUGACGGCACGGCCCCUUCCCACAGCAAGCCUGGGGCUGCCAGGAACUGCCCUUCAGAACCUUUGGGCCCAGGUCACCCUGAAGCCCCACAACUUUUUAUCUGGAUUAGUUAUUAAAAAACAAUAAAUUAAGCAACAACUUGGUCCUGAG